AGUCGCAGCGGUGACCGCGGGCGGGUGGGGCGCCGGGUAAGUGCUCGGGCCGGGCGGGGGGCGUACCCCGUUUGGCGUGCAGCCCUUUCUACAAGACCCCCAGUGCCCGAUCCUUCCGAGAAGAGGGGACCCCCCCCCGCAUCUCCGCUGUCCAGGCCUCGCCGUGGAGCCCCAGCAGGACCCCAGCCCUCGGUUGCCCUCGGCUCUGGCGUGUCCCGGCGCGGGCGGGCAGUGCUUCCCCUCGGCAGGGACUGGAGUCCAGGGGAGGGGAACGCGGGAGACGCUGGCCCUAGUGACCCCCCGAUCCCGGAGAGUUGGUGGUGAAGAAACCAAGACGCAGAGAGGCCAAGCCCCUUGCCUUGGGUCACACAGCCAAAGGAGGCAGAGCCAGAACUCACAACCAGAUCCAGAGGCAACAGGGACAUGGCCACCUGGGACGAAAAGGCCUUCCUCAGAACACGGAUCCCCUGGGGCAGGAAGGGAGAAGUGCUGGGGGCAGCUGAGCCUGCUGCUUGGAGUCCUCUUGCCUCCCCACAGAGAAGAGAUUUGCUCAGGGGUUUCAUUCCACCUUCCACCAUCCAGGAGGCAGUCACCCGCAGGGCCAAGGUGGCUCCCGCUGAGAGGAUGAGCAAGUUCUUAAGGCACUUCACGGUCGUGGGAGACGACUACCAUGCCUGGAACAUCAACUACAAGAAAUGGGAGAAUGAAGAGGAGGAGGAGGAGGAGGAGCAGCCACCACCCACACCAGUCUCAGGCGAGGAAGGCAGAGCUGCAGCCCCUGACGUUGCCCCUGCCCCUGGCCCCGCACCCAGGGCCCCCCUUGACUUCAGGGGCAUGUUGAGGAAACUGUUCAGCUCCCACAGGUUUCAGGUCAUCAUCAUCUGCUUGGUGGUUCUGGAUGCCCUCCUGGUGCUUGCUGAGCUCAUCCUGGACCUGAAGAUCAUCCAGCCCGACAAGAAUAACUAUGCUGCCAUGGUAUUCCACUACAUGAGCAUCACCAUCUUGGUCUUUUUUAUGAUGGAGAUCAUCUUUAAAUUAUUUGUCUUCCGCCUGGAGUUCUUUCACCACAAGUUUGAGAUCCUGGAUGCCGUCGUGGUGGUGGUCUCAUUCAUCCUCGACAUUGUCCUCCUGUUCCAGGAGCACCAGUUUGAGGCUCUGGGCCUGCUGAUUCUGCUCCGGCUGUGGCGGGUGGCCCGGAUCAUCAAUGGGAUUAUCAUCUCAGUUAAGACACGUUCAGAACGGCAACUCUUAAGGUUAAAACAGAUGAAUGUACAAUUGGCCGCCAAGAUUCAACACCUUGAGUUCAGCUGCUCUGAGAAGGAACAAGAAAUUGAAAGACUUAACAAACUAUUGCGACAGCAUGGACUUCUUGGUGAAGUGAACUAGACCCGGACCAGCUCCCCUCAAAAAGAAGACACUGUCUCAUGGGCCUGUGCUGUCACGAGAGGAACAGCUGCCCCUCCUGGGCCGCUUGGUGAGAGGUUUGGUUUGAUACCUCUGCCUCCCUCCUGCCAGCAUGGAUUCUGGGUGGACACAGCCUUGUGGAAGGUCCAGUACCACCAAGAGCUGCCCAUCCACUCCCACCCCACACUGUAUCAAAUGUAUCACAUUUUCUCAUGUUGAACACUUUAGCCUUAAUUGAAAAUGAGCAACAAAGCUGGACAAUUGCUAGUUGUAUAUAAAAUUUAAUCUCACCGAAUGUACAGUUUUCAAAUUUCACGUGUAUAUUAAGGAACUGAUGCAUCUGAGCAUUCUGAAAGAAAGAAAAAGAAGCUACUUUAGCUGCCACCCCAUUCUAGAAAAGUCUCUUAUUUUCAAGCUGUUCUAAAUAGCUUCGUCUCAGUUUCCCCAAAAGGGGUACCCAGGCCCCUCCUCUGUGUGCCCCAGCUGCAUCAGCCAGCUUCUAGGUGGCUCCAUUGUUUUCUGCCACCUGACAACAUUUUUCCUCAAUUACUGUACAACUACUGUAUAAAAUAAAACAACUACUGUAUAAAAUAAACUCUCUCUUUUCCCUGGACCCUCCUACUGUAUUCUUUCCUCUGUGGCACCCAUACCAGCCUGCCAGUCGGAGAGCAAGCUAGCUACAGUGCCUGGUGCAGAAAUGGCAAUU